AGCCGCGCAGCGGGAAGAGCCGGCCGAAGCGUGGCGGCCACAGACUGUGGGUACCGGGUCCGAGGGACUCGCGCUUUUCUCUCCGUGCCAUGGCGCCAGCGAAAGCCACGAACGUGGUGCGGCUGCUACUAGGCUCCACAGCGCUGUGGCUUUCGCAGCUCGGCUCCGGGACGGUCGCCGCGUCCAAGUCGGUGACUGCCCACUUGGCCGCGAAGUGGCCCGAGACCCCGCUGCUGCUGGAGGCAAGUGAAUUUAUGGCAGAAGAAAGUAAUGAAAAAUUUUGGCAGUUUUUGGAAACUGUGCAAGAAUUAGCAAUUUAUAAGCAAACAGAAUCAGAUUAUUCUUAUUACAACUUAAUCCUGAAGAAAGCUGGACAGUUUCUAGACAAUUUACACAUCAACCUUUUAAAGUUUGCUUUCUCUAUAAGGGCAUACUCCCCAGCUAUUCAGAUGUUUCAGCAGAUUGCAGCUGAUGAGCCACCACCAGAUGGUUGUAAUGCAUUUGUGGUUAUUCAUAAGAAGCACACCUGUAAAAUUAAUGAGAUUAAAAAGCUGCUGAAGAAAGCUGCUUCAAGGACUAGACCUUAUCUAUUUAAAGGAGAUCACAAAUUUCCUACAAACAAAGAGAACUUACCAGUGGUGAUUCUCUAUGCCGAAAUGGGUACUAGAACAUUUAGUGCAUUUCACAAAGUAUUGUCUGAAAAAGCUCAAAAUGAGGAAAUUCUGUAUGUUCUUCGCCAUUAUAUUCAGAAACCAAGCUCACGGAAAAUGUACUUAUCUGGGUAUGGUGUGGAGCUAGCAAUUAAGAGUACAGAAUACAAAGCACUGGAUGAUACCCAAGUUAAAACUGUGACUAAUACUACUGUAGAGGAUGAGACUGAAACAAAUGAAGUUCAAGGAUUUCUCUUUGGGAAACUAAAAGAAAUAUAUUCAGAUCUUAGAGAUAAUCUGACAGCAUUCCAAAAAUACCUGAUUGAGAGUAACAAACAAAUGAUGCCUUUGAAAGUCUGGGAACUACAAGAUCUUAGUUUUCAAGCAGCUUCUCAAAUAAUGUCCGCUCCAGUUUAUGAUUCCAUUAAAUUAAUGAAAGACAUUUCACAGAACUUCCCCAUAAAAGCCAGAUCUCUAACCAGAAUUGCUGUAAAUCAACAUAUGAGAGAAGAAAUAAAGGAAAAUCAAAAGGAUCUUCAAGUUAGAUUUAAAAUUCAGCCAGGCGAUGCUCGUCUAUUUAUAAAUGGCCUUCGUGUUGAUAUGGAUGUUUAUGACGCUUUUAGUAUUUUGGAUAUGCUGAAAUUAGAAGGAAAAAUGAUGAAUGGCCUUCGCAAUCUUGGGAUCAAUGGGGAAGAUAUGAGCAAAUUUUUAAAAUUAAAUUCACACAUUUGGGAAUAUACUUAUGUAUUAGAUAUUCGACAUUCUUCUAUAAUGUGGAUUAAUGACUUAGAAAAUGAUGAUUUGUAUAUUACAUGGCCUACAAGUUGCCAGAAACUUCUGAAGCCAGUAUUUCCUGGAAGUGUACCUUCCAUAAGGCGCAAUUUUCAUAAUUUGGUUCUGUUUAUUGAUCCGGCCCAAGAAUAUACCUUGGAUUUUAUAAAACUUGCUGAUGUUUUCUAUUCUCACGAAGUUCCUCUUAGAAUUGGUUUUGUGUUCAUUCUUAAUACAGAUGAUGAAGUUGAUGGAGCAAAUGAUGCUGGAGUUGCUCUCUGGCGAGCUUUCAACUAUAUUGCAGAAGAAUUUGAUAUAUCAGAAGCAUUUAUUUCUAUAGUACACAUGUACCAAAAAGUGAAGAAGGAUCAAAAUAUACUCACUGUGGACAAUGUGAAGAGUGUUCUCCAAAAUACAUUUCCUCAUGCUAAUAUUUGGGAUAUUUUGGGAAUUCAUUCUAAAUAUGAUGAAGAAAGAAAGGCUGGAGCAAGCUUUUAUAAGAUGACUGGCCUGGGUCCUUUGCCUCAAGCUCUUUAUAAUGGUGAACCCUUUAAACAUGAAGAGAUGAAUAUUAAAGAACUAAAAAUGGCUGUUCUUCAAAGAAUGAUGGAUGCAUCUGUAUAUUUACAAAGAGAAGUUUUUUUGGGCACAUUAAAUGAUCGCACGAAUGCAAUUGAUUUUCUAAUGGAUAGGAAUAAUGUUGUACCCCGUAUAAAUACUUUGAUUUUGCGUACUAACCAGCAGUACCUCAAUUUAAUAUCUACAUCAGUAACUGCUGAUGUUGAAGAUUUCUCUACUUUCUUUUUCUUGGAUUCACAAGAUAAGAGUGCUGUAAUUGCAAAGAACAUGUAUUAUUUAACCCAAGACGAUGAGAGUAUAAUUUCUGCAGUCACUCUCUGGAUUAUUGCAGAUUUUGAUAAGCCUUCUGGGAGAAAACUUCUUUUUAAUGCAUUAAAGCACAUGAAAACAAGUGUUCAUAGUCGGUUGGGGAUUAUUUAUAAUCCUACAUCAAAAAUAAAUGAAGAGAACACAGCUAUUUCUAGAGGAAUUUUGGCAGCUUUUCUUACACAGAAGAACAUGUUUUUGAGAAGCUUUCUUGGGCAACUGGCAAAGGAAGAAAUUGCUACAGCUAUUUACUCUGGAGAUAAAAUUAAAACAUUCCUUAUUGAGGGGAUGGAUAAGAAUGCUUUUGAGAAAAAAUAUAAUACUGUUGGAGUGAAUAUUUUUCGAACUCACCAGUUGUUCUGUCAAGAUGUACUUAAAUUACGUCCUGGAGAAAUGGGUAUUGUCAGCAAUGGGAGAUUCUUAGGACCUUUAGAUGAAGAUUUUUAUGCAGAAGAUUUUUACUUGUUGGAAAAGAUAACAUUUAGUAAUUUAGGAGAGAAAAUUAAAGGCAUUGUUGAAAAUAUGGGAAUCAACGCAAAUAACAUGAGUGACUUUAUUAUGAAAGUUGAUGCCCUUAUGUCCUCUGUGCCUAAGCGUGCAUCUCGAUAUGAUGUCACAUUUCUUAGGGAGAAUCACAGUGUUAUAAAGACGAAUCCUCAAGAGAAUGAUAUGUUCUUCAAUGUCAUUGCUAUUGUUGAUCCAUUAACAAGAGAAGCACAGAAAAUGGCACAGUUGUUGGUUGUACUUGGCAAGAUUAUCAACAUGAAGAUAAAGUUGUUCAUGAACUGUAGGGGCAGGCUUUCAGAAGCCCCUUUAGAAAGAAUCACUGUCAUUCAUUAUGAGCCAUUCUUAUUGAUGGGAAUAUUCAGUUCUCCUUCAUGUGUCAUUGGGCAGAAAACAGGCUUUUACCGUUUUGUUCUGGAACCAGAACUGAUGUCAGGGGCUAAUGACGUUUCUUCUCUUGGACCAGUGGCAAAAUUUUUGGAUAUUCCUGAAUCACCCCUCCUAAUCCUCAACAUGAUUACUCCAGAAGGCUGGUUGGUUGAAACAGUGCACAGCAACUGUGACCUUGAUAAUAUUCACUUAAAGGAUACUGAGAAAACUGUUACAGCAGAAUAUGAACUAGAAUACUUACUACUGGAAGGACAAUGCUUUGAUAAAGUGACAGAACAGCCUCCUCGGGGUCUGCAGUUCACACUAGGCACAAAAAAUAAACCUGCUGUGGUUGAUACAAUAGUGAUGGCACAUCAUGGGUAUUUUCAAUUAAAAGCAAACCCAGGUGCUUGGAUACUGAGGUUACACCAAGGAAAAUCUGAAGAUAUUUAUCAAAUAGUUGGGCAUGAAGGAACUGACUCUCAAGCAGACCUAGAAGAUAUCAUUGUUGUAUUAAACAGCUUCAAAAGCAAGAUACUCAAAGUAAAAGUGAAAAAAGAAACAGACAAAAUUAAGGAAGAUAUCCUUACCGAUGAAGAUGAAAAAACAAAAGGACUGUGGGAUUCCAUUAAAAGUUUCACAGUAAGCUUGCAUAAAGAAAACAAAAAGGAAAAAGAUGUCCUAAACAUUUUUUCAGUUGCUUCUGGUCAUUUAUAUGAACGUUUUUUAAGAAUUAUGAUGCUUUCUGUUUUGCGUAACACCAAAACACCAGUGAAAUUCUGGUUGCUAAAAAAUUAUCUCUCACCGACAUUUAAAGAAGUAAUUCCUCACAUGGCUAAAGAGUAUGGAUUCCGAUAUGAACUAGUUCAAUAUAGGUGGCCCCGUUGGCUUCGUCAACAGACUGAAAGACAGAGGAUUAUUUGGGGUUACAAAAUUCUUUUCCUUGAUGUUCUUUUCCCACUAGCAGUGGACAAAAUCAUUUUUGUUGAUGCUGACCAGAUUGUGAGACAUGAUCUAAAAGAACUUCGAGAUUUCGAUCUGGAUGGAGCUCCUUAUGGGUAUACUCCAUUUUGUGAUAGCCGCAGGGAAAUGGAUGGAUAUCGUUUCUGGAAAACAGGAUACUGGGCAUCACAUCUUUUAAGACGGAAAUACCAUAUCAGUGCUUUAUAUGUAGUGGAUCUCAAGAAGUUCAGGAGAAUUGGAGCAGGUGACAGGCUCAGGAGCCAGUAUCAAGCUCUCAGUCAAGAUCCAAACAGUCUUUCAAACCUAGAUCAGGAUCUCCCCAAUAAUAUGAUUUACCAAGUCGCCAUUAAGUCUCUUCCUCAAGACUGGCUGUGGUGUGAAACCUGGUGUGAUGAUGAAUCCAAACAAAGAGCCAAAACAAUUGAUCUGUGCAAUAAUCCCAAAACAAAAGAAUCCAAACUAAAAGCUGCUGCCAGAAUUGUCCCAGAAUGGGUGGAGUAUGAUGCUGAGAUAAGACAACUAUUAGAUCAUCUUGAAAACAAGAAGCAAGAUACAAGCUCUACAAGAAGCAUGGCAGCAUCUGCUUCUGGGGAAGCCUCAAGGAGCUUUUAUUCAUGGUGGAAGGCAAAGCAGGAGCAGGUGUCUUACAUUGGAGGAACAGGACCACGAGAGAGAAGGGGAAGGUGCCACACACUUUUAAACAACCAGAUCUCACACUAACUCACUCACUAUCACAAGAAGAGCACCGAGGGAAUGCUGCUAACCCAUUCAUGAGGACUCUGCCCCCGUGGUCCAGUUACCUCCUACCAGGGAAUUAUACCCUCCCACCUCCAACACUGGGGAUGAGAUUUGGUGAGGACACAGAUCCAAACCAUAUCGUUGUGCUUAUUGGCCAUCUGUAUAUUAUAAGUUUUUUUGCAAAGUGCCUAUUCAAGAUUUUUGCUCUUUUUUAAGUUUUGGAUUUUGAAUUUCUUUGGAAAACAAAAAAGCCCACUGAGAUUUUGAUUGCAACUCUUGUUUUAAAUCAGUUUGGUGAAGAUUAAUGUGUUGAUUAUGUUGAGCUUCCAAUUCAUAAAUACGAUAUGUUUCUUGAUUUAUUUUGGUCUUUAAUUACUCCUAGCAGAGUUUUAGUUUGCAGUGUACAUAUUUUACUAAGAAUUUUAUAACUGAAUGCUAAUAUAAAUGGUAUUUUUAAAUUUCUUGUUGGUUGCUAAUACAUAGAAAUACAAUUAAUUUUUGUAUAUUGGACUUAUGUCCUGUGGCUUUGCUAUACUCACUUAUUAGUUCUAGUAGAGUUCUUAGGAAUUUUUUCAUAAUGGGUCCUGUUAUAGUUGUAGAGUUCACAGGAUUGUCUUCACAGUGGAUCAUAUCUUCAGCAAAUAAAAAUAGUUUUACUUUUUCCUUUCCA